ACAUUCACUGGGCAAGCCGACUGUGAGCCAGGAAGUGCUCUUGGGGAGCCCAGGCCAAGCCAUCCAUUCUUGGGUCCUUUGGAGGGUAGAUAUGGAUUCCCAGUUUCUCCAGCGGCCAGUGCUCCCCCUAGUCCACACAGUGAGACCGUGAAAGCAGAUGCUCCGGGGCACUCCUGGGCAGCUUUUGCUCAGUGGAUGAUGGGUGACUACAGACUCCCUGACCACCCCCAGCCCAUGGAAAUUCUCAACCUGUACUUGGGAGACAGCCUGGAGCCCCACCCAGGAGAGUGCCCAAGGGAAACGUGCAGCCAUGAGGAUCCACCGGAGCCUUUCGAGGAGCAAACCUGGGCCACUGACCCUCCUGAACCUACCAGACAAAAUGUUCCUCCCUGGGGCUCCGGUGUGGAGCUCACACACCUGGGGAGCUGGGUCCAUCAGGACGGGCUGGAGCCUUGCCAGGAGCAAACCCGGGCCACUGACCCUCCUGAAUCUACCAGACAAGAUGCUCCUCCCUGGGGCUCCGGUGUGGAGCUCACACACCUGGGGAGCCCCUCUGCCCAGAGGGAGCACAGGCAGAACACAGCAUCACCAGGGUCACCAGUGAACAGCCAUCUACCGGGGAGCCCAAAGCAGAACCGGAGCACGUCCACACAGGUAGUGUUCUGGGCAGGCAUCCUGCAGGCCCAGAUGUGUGUCCUAGACCUGGAGGAGGAGCUGGAGAAGACGGAAGGGCUCAAGGCUGGGCUGAAAUGCUGUCUCCCCACGCCCCCUGUGGACCUCCCCGGGGACACGGGCCUGCACUCCAGCCCACCUGAGAAUGAAGACUCAGGGGAAGACAGCAGUGAGCCUGAGGGAGAGGGCCAGGCAUGGCUGAGAGAGGGAACCCCAGACUCUUCCCCACAGUGGGGAGCUGAGGAGGAGAGCAUGUUCUUCAGCAACCCCCUCUUCCUGGCGAGUCCUUGCUCAGAGAACAGUGCUUCUGGAGAGUGCUUUUCCUGGGGGGCUUCAGACUCCCAUGCAGGUGUGAGGACUGGACCUGAGAGCCCAGCGACUCUGGAGCCUCCCCUCCCAGAAGACACAGUGCUGUGGGAGCUGGAAAGUGAGCCAGAUUUGGGGGACGGCGCUGCUAUCAGUGGGCAUUGUACCCCUCCAUUCCCUGUGCCCAUCUAUAAACCACACUCCAUCUGCUGGGCCUCAGUGGCUGCCGCUGAGGGGGCUCCUGCAGCACCUCCUGGUCACGGGGAGAGUGAGGGAGAUAGGCUUGGUCCUGCUCCAUCUGCAGCACCGUGUGUGGACGAAGCAUUGACCUGGGAAUCAGGAUGUGUCGGAUCUGAUCUUGGCCCUGCUGCACAUCCUGUGCAACCUUGGGCCUCUCUCAGCCCUGAGGGCUGGCAGAGAGGAGGUCCUUUUUGGCCCCAGGUGACUCUUAACUCCCAGGACAGAGAUGAGAGGGAGGGUGGACACCCCCAGGAAUCUCUUCCCUGCACCUUGGCCCCCUGCCCCUGGAGGAGCCCAGCUUCUUCUCCAGAGCCUAGCAGCCCAGAAUCUGAGAGCAGAGGCCCUGGUCCCAGGCCCAGCCCUGCAUCGUCCCAGGAGGGCAGCCCGCAGCUUCAACACCACAGCUCAGGCAUUUUGCCCAAGUGGACACUAGAUGCUUCACAGUCUUCACUCUUGGAGACGGAUGGGGAACAGCCAAGUUCCUUGAAGAAAAAGGAGGCAGGGGAGGCCCCAAAACCAGGCGAGGAAGUAAAGAGUGAAGGAACAGCCAGGCCUGCAGAGACUGGAGACGUCCAGCCUGACAUUCACCUGACUUCUGCAGAACAUGAGAAUCUGAGGACACCGAUGAACUCUUCUUGGCUUCCUGGGAGCCCUAUGCCCCAAGCACAGUCCCCAGAGGAAGGCCAGAGACCACCAGCUGGAGACAAGCUAGCUAAUGGCGUCAGGAACAACAAGGUAGCCUGGAACUUGGCCUCACGCCUCUAUCGCCUGGAGGGCUUCCGGAAGUCUGAAGUGGCUGCCUACCUGCAGAAGAACAAUGACUUUAGCAGGGCUGUGGCUGAGGAGUACCUGUCCUUCUUCCAGUUUGGAGGCCAGAGUCUGGACCGAGCCCUCCGGAGCUUCCUCCAGGCCUUGGUGCUCAGUGGGGAGACUCAGGAACGGGAGCGAAUCCUCUACCAGUUCUCCAGACGCUUCCACCAUUGCAAUCCGGGGAUCUUCCCCUCAGUAGAUUCUGUACACACCUUGACAUGUGCAAUCAUGCUGCUUAACACGGACCUGCAUGGACAGAACAUUGGGAAGAGCAUGAGCUGCCAGGAAUUCAUAACCAACCUGAAUGGGCUGAGGGAUGGCGGGAACUUCCCCAAGGAGCUGCUGAAGGCCCUCUACUGGUCUAUCCGCAGCGAGAAGCUCGAGUGGGCCGUGGAUGAAGAAGACACAGCCAGACCUGAGAAGGCCCAGCCGUCCCUGCCAGCUGGCAAGAUGAGCAAGCCCUUCCUUCAGCUGGCUCAGGAUCCCACAGUGCCCACCUACAAGCAGGGCAUCCUGGCUCGGAAAAUGCAUCAAGAUGCAGACGGCAAGAAGACGCCAUGGGGCAAGCGUGGCUGGAAGAUGUUCCACACCUUACUGCGAGGGAUGGUUCUCUACUUCCUGAAGCAGGGAGAAGACCACUGUCUGGAGGGGGAGAGCUUGGUGGGGCAGAUGGUGGAUGAGCCCGUGGGGGUGCACCACUCGCUGGCCACCCCCGCCACGCAUUACACCAAGAAGCCGCACGUCUUCCAGCUGCGCACGGCUGACUGGCGCCUCUACCUCUUCCAGGCACCCACUGCCAAGGAGAUGAGCUCCUGGAUCGCGCGCAUCAACUUGGCUGCGGCCACGCACUCCGCGCCGCCCUUCCCCGCCGCUGUGGGCUCCCAGCGCAGAUUCGUGCGGCCCAUCCUGCCCGUGGGCCCCGCCCAGAGCUCCCUGGAGGAGCAGCAUCGAUCCCACGAGAACUGCCUGGACGCUGCCGCGGACGACCUGCUGGAUCUACAGAGGAACCUGCCGGAGCGGCGGGGCCGUGGCCGCGAGCUGGAGGAGCACCGCCUGCGGAAGGAGUACCUGGAGUACGAGAAAACCCGCUACGAGACCUACGUGCAGCUGCUGGUGGCCCGCCUGCACUGCCCCUCUGAUGCUCUGGACCUGUGGGAGGAGCAGCUGGGGAGGGAAGCUGGAGGCACUCGGGAGCCCAAGCUCAGCCUGAAGAAGUCCCACUCGAGCCCGUCCCUGCACCAGGAUGAGGCUCCCACCACGGCCAAGGUGAAGCGCAACAUCUCAGAGCGCAGAACCUACCGGAAGAUCAUCCCUAAGCGGAACCGCAAUCAGCUGUGAAGCCAGCACCACCUCAGAGACACUGUUCCCUGCUCCAGGGUAGACCUGAGAUGAACCUCCCUGGAGGAGACUUAUUUCAAUGAGUCCACCAUGACGGAUGAGGCACCUCCUUUCCCUGCUGAAGGACAAACCUUGUUUCCCUGUGGCCCUCAUUCUUGUGCUCCCUGAAGCUUUCCUAAUAUUGCUGUGCUCCCCACCACCCCCAUGGCAGUCCCUCCGCAGCCCCAGUCCCUGGCCACGCCCAAGGGAAGAGGGAGGUGAGGACUUGACUUUCCUCCCAGAGCUCAGCCCAUGUCACCCUCCAGGCCCCAGAAUCCAGAGUGGCCUCAUUUCCUAGACUUGCUGAGAACUCAGCACUUGUUUGAGAACCAGUGCUUAUGUGGUGUGCCCUUGGCUUCUGGGGGAGAGCUUGGGGCAGCAGAGGCCCCUGGGCAGCCCAGCCAGGGGAGCCACAGCCCCAAGGAUGGUCUUGCUCUGGGAAUUAGGUGACCUUCCUGGGGAGGCCCCAGGAGAGUGAAUCAGGGACUCUUGAGAAAUUCCUAACCAGCCUCCUGUGACCCAGGGAGCAGGGUCGCUAAGGUCCUGCCCACUGAGGGGACAGCCUUCUGGGCAGGGACCUCGGGGGGCUUCAAGGGCUCUGCACGGCUGUGGGGCCCUGUGCCUUUGUCUCCUUGUGUCUCCUUUCCCCCGAAGUAGAUGAAACAGUCUCACAUACCCAACUGCUCAUCAACAGAGCAGAGCUGAUGGCAUGAGUGAGGGCUGGGCGGGGUGGGGCCUCCAGAGCUUUGCAGGGAACCCUGGAACCCUAGGAACAAGGAGCCUUUGUUCCAACAGAGCAGAGAAGGAGGUUCUCUAUGUUCAGACCACUGGAGAGGAUAGAGAGGUAAAAGGUGGCGACAGUUUCCCUUAGGGGUCUGCCUGGCAGGAGCCACAGCUCAGGAGAGUUGUGAGGGAUGGGACGGAGGCUGGCGACCAGGCGAGGCCUAGGCCAGGCUCGGGAGACUUUUCUGUGCUCCUUUCUACACAUGCCUUAAACCUUCCUUCCUGUGGGGUGCCUGGACCCCUUCCCCAUCUCUGGCAGCUCAGAGGGUCUCUGCUGCUCUCCCCUGGGAAAUCCCCUCAUCCUGCCCUCUGGCUGCCUCCCAGCUGGGCUUGUUCUCUGAGGGAGGUUCCGGAGACUCAUGGACUUGGGGCUCUGCCUGUAGGAAGGAGGCUGGGCCGGAGGGACCAGCCACCAUUGUCUCUGUUCAGCCAAGUGUGCAAGUAGGCUGCCCGCCAAGAGGGGGCCUCUGCUACCCGCUGCUGCCUGCCGGCUGACACACUGCCUCCCCAGCCUUCCUGCUAGGCCACCCUCCUCCCUUCCCAUGCUUGUAACCAGCUCUGGGGCUUGCACCUCCACAAAGUAAGGUUGGCCCUUGGAGGCCAUGUUUGGGUCUCCGGCCAGGGCCUAGGGCUAGGCCAUGCACCCAAUGGGUGCACAAUAAAUAACAGGUCAACAAAGAGGGAGGUGUGUCAGUGUGUGAGGAAGGGAGGUCAGGCAGCUAGGACCACCUGCAGUGUGGCAGGCUUCAUCCCUCUUUGCUCCAAGUGUGUAUGUGUGUCUGUGCAUGUGUGUAGUGUCUGUGUCUGUGUGUUCAUGCAUAUGCAGGAGUCACACGGUCAUAGGCCAUCAAAGCUGGAGGAGACCUCAGAAUCAUUCAUUCACCUACUUGCUCAUUUAUUCAUUCAUUCAUUUUGCAGAUAAUAUGGGACGCUUUCUAUGUGCCAGUACCAGGGGAUUCACAAAUGAAUUAAACAUGUCCCUGACUCCAUGAGUUGACAAUCUUGCCCACUGGUUUCCUGCUCUCAGUUUACAGAGGCACUUUUAUCUUGCUGGGGAAGUGUGCUGAAAAGACACAUUCCCAGCCCACACCCAGGGAUGCUGAUUCAGUCAGCCUGGGUCAGAGGGAUAGAUAAAUAUGUUUAAAGCUCCUUGGGUAAUUCUGAUGUGUAAGUAGCAGUUAGCUGCAGUAGAGUCCAAUUGCCUCAUUUGAUUGAAGUGGAAUCCCAGCAUCAAGUGGACAUGACUUUUGGCCCAAGACUGAUGCUUACAAACUAAGUGGAGUAGGUUAUUUGACCUCACUGAACAUGCAUCCUUUUUUUUUUUUUUUUUUUUUUUUUUUUUUGGAGACGGAGUUUCGCUCUUGUAACCCAGGCUGGAGUGCAAUGGUGUGAUCUUGGCUGACUGCAACCUCCACUGAAUCAAGCGAUUCUCCUGCCUCAGCCUCCCAAGUAGCUAGGAUUACAGGCGUGUGCCACCACGCCCGGCUAUUUUUUGUAUUUUUAGUAGAGAUGGGGUUUCGUCAUGUUGGCUAGGCUGGUCUCGAACUCCUGACCUCAGGUAGUCUGCCUGCCUCGGCCCCCCAAAGUGCUGGGAUUACAGGCGUGAACCACCACACCUGGCCUAUGCAUCCUUAUUUCUAAAACCAUGAUAAAAGGUGAAAGUCUGAAUGCAUGUGUGUGUGACACUUUGAUGCUCCUUUGCUCAUGUAGAACCGGCACCUCUCUUUCACCUGAGCACGUGGAAUCUUCAGAGCCAGAUGAUGGUGGCUGCCUGGCCUGCCAUAGUCAAUGCUGCCCAGGCACCUCUGCCUGGAGGGUCUGGGUUGUGGGCUGCAGUUAUGACAUGUGACCACUUGGAGGCAGGCUUGCAUCUUUCUAGCUUCUGGCUGCUCAGGUGUCCUGCUGUGGAGCUGAGCUGUGCUCCCUGAAAGGCAGGAAGUUAUUAUGUGUGCCCCUGUGCCAUCACCGAACCAGGACCUUCAACUUCGUAAAACCCACAGUGGCCUGGGCCAGGACUCCCACCAUCUAGGGAAGCCUCUCCUAGGGAAAAGACUGGGGCUCUGACAUCUUCCUGCAGAUGGAGAGAAAGAAAGACAUCUCAGAAGUCUAUGGGGACAGCCUACAGCUCCCCACAGGGUUGCUCCAGGUAACGCUGGAAGGUGAAAGCUGAGCAGGCUCCAGUCCCCAUCCUAGGUAUGGAACAGAUCAAACCACCACAGGCCUAUGUCUGACCUUGUUCCCACCCCAUGCUCCUCUCCCACCUGUGUCCUUCUCUUUGCAGGAGAAGGGACAGACAGAGGUUCUCAGUGAUGAGCUCAGGCUCUGGAAGGGCACUUGAAGUUUGGCUUUAGUUCUUCCUUUCCCAUAUAGGGGAGCUCAGCUUCCAGGGUCCUGGGCCUGCUGUGACCCAGGUUGUUACUCCUGAUAUAACUGCUUCCUGGGCUCUCAUGAUCUCAGCUGAGCCUGGCUUUCUGCUGAUGAUAUUUGUUUGUUGCUUGCCAGGCACCAGGGUAGAUAAAAAGAUCACCAAGACCCGCACCUUUUUCCUUAGGAGGGUCUGAGUCUUCAGGAGACGGAGACAUAUGGAAUGUGUCGGGGUUGGAAGGAGCAGGACUGGAGGGUCGGGGUGAGGGGGGCAGAGGGAAACAGGGCCGUCAGGGUGGCCUGAGGCCAGAUCAUACAGGGUCUCCAAUGCAGCCAAGGAGAGUGGCUUUUUGUGAAUGUGCAGUGCAACUUUUUUUUUUUUUUGAGACAGAGUCUCGCUCUGUUGCCCAGGCUGGAGUGCAAUGGUGCGAUCUCAGCUCACUGCAACCUCCGCCUCCUGGGUUCAAGAGAUUCUCCUUUCCCAGCCUCCCAAGUAGCUGGGAUUACAGGCAUGCACCACCAUGCCCAGCUAAUUUUGUAUUUUUUAGUAGAGACAGGGUUUCACCAUGUUGGUCAGGCUGGUCUCAAACUCCUGACCUCAAGUGAUCCAGCUGCCUCGGCCUCCCAAAGCAUUGGGAUCACAGGCGUGAGCCAACGUGCCUGGCCAGUGCAGUGCAAUUUUUAAAGAGAAGAGUGCCAAGCUCAGGGCUUGGAGGACAGCCUAGGGAUUUUGUUUUAAGAAGAUGAGCUGGGCGCGGUGGCUCAUGCCUGUAAUCCCAGCACUUUGGGAGGCUGAAGCGGGCGCAUCACCUGAGAUCAGGAGUUCGAGACCAGCCUGGCCAACGUGGUGAAACCCAGUCUUUACUAAAAAUACAAAAAAUAGCCGGGCAUGGUGGCACAUGCCUAUAAUCCCAGCUACUCAGGAGGCUGAAGCAGGAGAAUGGCUUGAACCCAGGAGGCGGAGGUUGCAGUGAGCUGAGGUUGCGCCAUUGCACUCCAGCCUGGGUAACAGAGCGAGACUCUGUCGAAAAAGAAAAAAAAGAUGAAAUGCCUUGAAAAAGUAAGGCCAAUGGGUAGGGUCAGAAUAUGGCCUGCAAAUGCACUGUACUAUUUGUGUAACUUAUAUGUAAAUCUGAAAUUAUUUCAAAAUAAAUACAAAAAGAAAAAAAGGCAAUAUCCCAGAACCUUGUGAAAACCUGGCCGUAGCAGGUCCUUUUUCCUCCUGCUGAGCUGAGCAGGCAUGCUCACAGAUCCUCAAGGUUUCUUGAAUGGCUACUGUCCUCCCCACUGGCCCCUCUGCCAACACCUCUGCCCCUCAGCUUUUCUGAUGCCCAUGCCCCCUCACCAGCUAACUGUGGCUUGCACCUUUACCUGUUCCCUUCAUUUUCCCUUCUCCAGAGGAAGAGGUGCUCUCCACAAGCCUGUGACCAACUGUUCCCCUCAGCCGGCACACUGGCUCCUCUUCUCCUGCCUGCCACAGACCUCUCUCCUUCAUGGGCCCACUGGGGCUCUUUGAGCCUAUUCUCUACCCCCUUCAUUAUCAUGCCUUGCAAACACCAUCAUGAGCAAAAAUCAAAGCUGGUGUUAGACUCUCUUGCUUUCCAUAGCUGACCCUGGCUUCCCUGCUUUCUGUGAUGAAUUCACGGUAUGUGUGGGCUUUGCCAACUGUUCCCAGCCCUUACCAGGUUCCCAUUCAUACCUGGCUCUAAUUCACACCUUACAAAUCGGCGUCCACCCCACCUUUGCCUGAAAUGGCACCUCCUAGGGCAAUUGAUGGCUGCAGUCAUCAACUCUGAUGCCUUCUCAGCCUUCUUCCGCCAUCACCUCUCAGCGACCUUUGGCCUUGAUAGCUAUGUGAUCAUCUACCAGACCCUGCACCCAGGCUCAGCCUGAUCUUGCCCCAGUGGCCAGGCCCUUGAGUGGGACUGCCGGGAAUUGAGUCCAGCUUUUCUAGCCAUCUGACCGUGGCCAGUUAGCCUCUUAUGUUCUGUUUGCUUCUCUAUAAAAUGGGGAUAAUAACACUACUUAUGUCACAAGGUCCUCAUGAAGAUUAAGUGAAAUUAUGCACGUAAACAUCUCAGAACAAUGCCUGGCACAGAAGGGACACCUGUGAGGUUAGCUAUUAAUUCAUAGCCUCACCAGACUUACCCCACGUCUGCUCCCCUCCUCCUUUGGGCUCUGGCUUAGGCUCUGCCCUCAUGCAUGCCAUCCUGCUUGGAUGCUGGGUAGCUUUGCACUUGGCUCUGCCUUGGCCUGCAAAUAACAAAUCUGAGCUCAAAUGAGCUUUAGCAGAAAAGGACUUUGAUUGGCUCCAAUAGCUGAAUAAUCUGUAUCCAGGUCAGGUGAGGCUUCAUCUCGGGCUUCACUCUGAUUCAAGGCCCCUUUUCUCUCUUGUUCUUUUGGGGGCUCCAUCUCCCAGGCCUAUGAGCAGGAACAACCCUCAUGCUUCCAAGAUGGCCCCAGGAACUCUCAAGAUCCAUUUUCUUGGUGCAAAUAUAGCAGAAAGUGACUCUCUGCUUCCUGGAAGUUUCAAACUCAAAUCCAGGAAUAGUCUCCUGUAGCAGCCUGCCUUGGGCCGUGUGCCCAUAUCUGAGCCAGUCACUAGAGCCAGGGGUUUAAGGAGAUCAGAGUCCACUUCUGGAGAGGAUGAGAGUGAAGUCAGCACCACCAAAACAUAGGGACCAGCUGUGGAGAAAUUGUGAGUACUGGAAGGACAGGAUAGGAGGAAUGGAUGAUGGGGAGAAAACCGACUAAUAUGCAGAUGCCCUUUCCUCCAAGAGGCCUUCCCUAAGUCUUCCUCCUUCAGUUUCUAUUACAUGAAACUCUGUAACUCUCCUCUCCUCUCUCCUCUUCUUUUUUUUUUUUUUUUUUUUGAGAUGGAGUCUUGCUCGGUCGCCCAGGCUGGAGUGCGGUGGCAUGAUCUCGGCUCACUGCAAGCUCUGCCUCCCGAGUUCACGCCAUUCUCCUGCCUCAGCCUCCCGAGUAGCUGGGACUACAGGCGCCCGCUACCAUGCCCGGCUAAUUUUUUUGUAUUUUUAGUAGAGACGGGGUUUCACCGUGUUAGCCAGGAUGGUCUCAAUCUCCUGAUCUUGUGAUCCGCCUGCCUCAGCCUCCCAAAGUGCUGGGAUUACAGGCGUAAGCCACCACGCCCCGGCCCUCUUCAUUUCUUUUUGCCUCUCUGCUUCCAGAGCAACAUAAACUCCCUGUGGGCAGGAACUGGGAUUGUUGAUUUCCACUGCUUCCCCAGGGCCUGAUAUCUAGAGUCGAAAGAAUGCACAUCUCAAAACUAUGUCCUGGUUCUUUUUCUACUUUCUUGCAUAUUCUUUUUCAGGCAGGAGUGCAGUGGCACGAUCUCAAUUCACUGCAACCUCUGCCUCCCGGGUUCAAGCAAUUCUCCUUCCUCAGCCUCCUGAGUAGCUGGGAUUACAGGCAUGCACCACCACACCCAGCUAAUCUUUGUAUUUUCAGUAGAGAUGGGGUUUCACCAUGUUGGUCAGGCUGGUCUCAAACUCCUGACCUCGUGAUCCGCCGGCCUCUGCCUCCCAAAGUACUGGUGCAUAUUCUUUUUCUGUCUUUCCUGCUACUCCCUCUUGCUCUUCCCACCCCUAAACUAUGUAGCCUCAAAGAUCUUACCUGGCUGACUGCUGGGCUUUCAAGAUAGUUUCUGGAAGAAGUCUCUAAAUCUAAGCCUUCAACUCUCAUCUCUGUUCUGAAUUUCAGACCUGGAAUUCUAACUGUCCACAAUACAUGGCUCCUCAAUAUAUCUUCCUGAAAUUACAAAUGACCAUACGGUACAGGUGUUACUAUAUUACCUGUAAGACCACACUCGGUGUCAUCUCCUGCAAACUAGUCCUCUCCUGACUCCUCUGUUUCUGUGAGUGAUUCUGCGAUGGCUUGAGGUCAUCCGUUUGCUUUGAAAGAUCACACACCAGGAUACAUACAGAGAUGUGACCCGGAUGGAUGGACCUUUGCCUCACAAUCAGGGUAGAAGCCUCUGGUUUUCUUAUUUCUUUGUCCUCCUCUGUGGUGUGACACAGGUUCAGGAGGAGGUACCCAGACACAGAAGAGAUGCUUUCCCUGUGCAGGCUUGCUGACAGUCUUGCCCACCACUCCUGGCCUCCUCCCUCUACAUGUCCACAUUCGCUGCUCUGACCCUGAGUUGGACCCAGCUAGGAAUUGUGACUUCAGUUACUAGUAUUUCCUCUGAGCCUCUAGUCAUGGUCAUGGGCUAAUCUGUAUAUGAAAACCCACUUGAAAGAAAUCCCAGUGCUGAAGAAAGAAUUGAAACAUACAGAUCGUUUCUUUGCUCAAGGGAGUGUGGAUUUCAGUGCUCUCACUGAGCAGAGGCUGAGGGUGACCACCUUGGAUCUUCCUGCAGGACACAGCCCAGAGAAACUGAGCCUGAAUUUGCUGCCAUGUUUUGAGGACAUUAUCCACGCUAGUCUCUUUCAUCUGGGCCGAGGUGGGUAAUUUUCCUUAGAGUCAAGUACUAGAAAAAGUUUUGCUUCUUCUAAGAGCUGGUACAUUGCCCUCUUGUGAAUGAGAGCCAUGUAUGUGACCACAACACCCUUUCAGUUGACCACUAAGAGACUGAAGGCCAAUUCCGGAUCAACUUUACAGCCGCCUACGGCCUGCUAUACCACCCAUGGCAUAGUUUCUGUGGUCUGAUGCUUUAUUUUUUAUUGCAUUUUACUAAUUUAUGGCAUGCAUAUCAUAUGAGCAGUCUCAAAUCCUCCCCAGAACAAGGUGAGGAAUAUAUUAAUAUUUAAAAUAAAAUAAACAAAAUGUCA